AGUCCAGCACUAAAGGAUCCCCACUAAGGGCUGUUCACCUGCCCCAGGGACUCAGAACACACAUGACUCUCCCCACUUGAGCUCAGGAUCCCGGCAUUACACGGGGCGCGCUGAGCCCCAGAUGUCCCUAACCCCUUUCCAGCACCCUCCAGCCUUGCAGAAGCAGCCACCAUGCCAGUCUCUAAGUGCCCAAAAAAGUCGGAGUCCCUGUGGAAGGGGUGGGACCGGAAGGCCCAGAGGAACGGCCUGCGGAGCCAGGUAUACGCUGUGAAUGGCGACUACUAUGUGGGCGAGUGGAAGGACAACGUGAAACACGGGAAAGGAACACAGGUCUGGAAGAAGAAAGGAGCCAUCUAUGAGGGGGACUGGAAGUUUGGGAAGCGAGACGGCUACGGCACCCUCAGCCUUCCUGACCAACAGACAGGAAAGUGCAGGAGAGUCUACUCAGGCUGGUGGAAAGGUGAUAAGAAAUCGGGUUAUGGGAUCCAGUUUUUCGGACCCAAGGAGUAUUAUGAGGGUGACUGGUGUGGCAGCCAGCGCAGCGGGUGGGGCCGCAUGUAUUACAGCAACGGCGACAUCUACGAGGGACAGUGGGAGAACGACAAGCCCAACGGGGAGGGCAUGCUGCGCCUGAAGAACGGGAACCGCUACGAGGGCUGCUGGGAGAGAGGCAUGAAGAACGGGGCGGGGCGUUUCUUCCAUCUGGACCACGGCCAGCUGUUUGAAGGCUUCUGGGUGGACAAUAUGGCCAAAUGCGGGACGAUGAUCGACUUUGGCCGUGACGAGGCCCCUGAGCCCACUCAGUUCCCCAUUCCUGAGGUCAAAAUCCUAGACCCUGAUGGUGUGCUGGCGGAGGCCUUGGCCAUGUUCAGGAAGACAGAGGAAGGAGAUUGAUGCCAGAGAACACAAACGCUUCAGGAGAAAUUCAAGCCUGUGUCACCCGAUCGCUCAGACCAGUGCGGCUCUGGCUGGAGGAGUCAGCAGCAGCUCCAGGCAUGACCCCGGCACCCUCAUAGGGCCCCUCACUACCCCCAGCACUGGGUCAUUUCUUGCCAAUAGGAAGGCUGGUGCUUCUCUCCCAGGCUGUCCUCGGGACCCUCUUCAUUCUCUGAUCUCAUCCUGGAAUGCAUGAGAAUAAAGAAUAACCAAGUGGUAUAAGCCUGGGCCUAUGGGAUAAGGAUGGGGCACUCGAGGGGGCUCAGCAGGGCUUUCAGGUUUAGAAGAGGGAAGACCUGCCUUGGCUGGGCUGCCUGGGUUUAGCUUGGGGGAGUAAGGGCAGGUCUUAGGCCGGGUGCAGUGGCUCAUUCCUGUAAUCCCAGAACUUGGGAGGCCAAGGUAAGAGGACUGCCUGAGGCCAGGAGUUCGAGACCAGCUUAGGCAACAUAGCAAGACCCUGACUCUACAAAAAAAAAUUUUAAAAUAUAAAAGAAAGGAAAAGAAAAAGAGAAAGAAAUGGCAGGUCCCCUGUGAGAUAACCCAGAUGACCCAGAGAGAAGGCCUGUAUCCUGCCACACUGGCUGCCAAGAUUGGAGAUCAUAAAAUUUCCUGACCACUUCUCAGCCUAACACAGGGCUCUCAACCUUGAAAUCCCAUGGAAACUUUGCAAAGCUGUGGAAGCCCAGGUCCCAUGCCCAGAGAUUCACAGGUUCACAUCUAAUUCAUCUGGGGUGAGGCCUGAGCUUUCAGAAAAUUCCCCAGGUGAUUUUUUUUUUUUAAGACGUAGUCUCCCUCUAUUGCCCAGGCUGGAAUGCAGUGGCGCGAUCUCAGCUCACUGCAACCUCUGCCUCCCAUGUUCAAGCGAUUCUCCUACCUCAGCCUCCUGAGUAGCUGGGAUUACAGGCGCAUGCCACUGAGCCCAGCUAAUUUUUGUAUUUUUAGUAGAGAUGGGGUAUCACCAUGUUGGUCAGGCUGGUCUUGAACUCCUGACCUCGUGAUCUGCCCCGCUCAGUCUCCUAAAGUGCUGGGAUUACAGGUGUGAGCCAUCGAGCCUGGCCUUUUUUUUUUUUUUUUUUUUUUUUUUGAGACAGAGUCUUGCUCUGUCACCCAGGCUGGAGUGCAGUGGCACAAUCUCGGCUCACUGCAACCUCGCCUCCCUGGUUCAAGCGAUUAUCCUGCCUCAGCCUCCCAAGUAGCUGGGAUUACAGGCACCUGCCACCAAGGCUAAUUUUUUGUAUUUUUAGUAGAGACAGGGUUUCACCAUGUUGGCCAGGACGGUCUCGAUCUCCUGACCUCGUGAUCUGCCCGCCUUGGACUCCCAAAGUGCUGGGAUUACAGGUGUGAGCCACUGCUCCCAGCCAAGAUCAGAUGUUCUUGCAUAAUGGGCAGGUGAGCUCUGGAGUCACAGUGCCUGGGCGUGAAUCUCGGAGCUGUGUGUUCUCAGGAAUGUCACCCAAACUCUGUUCUGUUGGUCUCCUCACUUGCAAUAUGGGGCAUUAACAGUACUUACCACCUGGGGUUACUGUGGUUAGUUACUGUGAGGAUGAGAUAAGGCGGUGGUUUUAAACUGUGGGUAGGAUUUUGUCCUCCCUCAGCCCCACUCUUUCUUGGGGACAUUUGGCAAUGUAUGACAUUUUUGAUGUCACAACAGGCAGGAAGAAGGCUACUGGCAUUGAGUGAGUAGAGACCAGGGAUGCGGUUAAGCAUAGUGCAAUAUCACCAUGCUACAAAAAAAAAAAAAAAAAAGAAUUCAGCACCUGUAAUCCCAACUACUUGGGAGGCUGAGGCAGGAGAAUUGCUUGAACCUGGGUGGCAGAGGUUGCAGUGAGCCGAGAUUGCGCCAUUGCACUCCAGCCUGGGCGACAGAGCGAGACACCAUCUCCAAAAAAAAAAAAAAAAAAAAUGUUGAGAAACCCUGAAAUACCACGAUUCUAGCUAAGACCUCAGCAAGAGGCACAUAGCACAUAGUAAAGCCUCAAUAAACACCACUGACCUUACUGAGGUUCUCUCUGCCCCCUAAGUCAUAAGUAGGGUGGCCUCACCAAGGGUGUGGUUCUCAGUCUGUACCUCUGGCACUGGGAAGCCCCGCCUGGCCACCCUAGGAUGCAGAAUUAAUCAUAACUUCCAGAUAUGGAGCACUCACUCUAUUCCAGGCCGUGUGCUGACAGCUUCGCAGCAAGCAUUCUCUCCUGGCACUCCCCGACAACAGUGAGGUGUCUUGCUAUUACUGCCAUUUUAGAGGAGGAAACAGGUUCAGGGAGGAUCACAAGUCAUCAAGCUAGUACUGUGCUUAAACUUAGGUCUAGCUGUUCUUAAUGUGCAGAAGAGUGUAAAGGGUUACCAUUUUUAAAGAAAAAGUGGGGGCAGGGCAUGGUGGCUCAUGCCUGUAAUCCUAGCACUUUGAGAGGCCGAGGCAGGCGGAUCAAGAGGUCAGGAGUUCGAGACCAGCCUGACCAACAUGGUGAAACCCUGUCUCUACUAAAAAUACAAAAAUUAGCUGGGUGUGGUGGAGUGCAUCUAUAAUCCCAGCUACUCAGGAGGCUGAGGCAGGAGAAUCACUUGAACCCAGGAGGCGGAGGUAGUGGUGAGCCAAGAUCACGCCGAGCCGAGAUCGUGCCGCUGCUCUCCAGCCUGGGCAACAGAGCGAGACUCCAUCUCAAAAAAAAAAAAAAUGUUGGAAGAGGGUGUGCUUGUUUAUGUACAAAAUGUCGCUAGAUUUAAACACAAUAAACUGGCAAAGAUGGUUGUCUCUGGGGAGAAUUGGGGACUUGGGAACAGGAGCUGAAGAACAACUUUUCAGUGUUGUGUUUGGAACCAUGUGAAUGUAUUAUGUAUUCAAAAUGUAAAUAAAAAUGAAGUUAAAGAGA